ACCAAAAAAGCUGAAACAAUAAUACAAUGAAUGAAUACAUCUGUAGGUAUUAUUGAGAUGUAGCUAUUGUACCAUUUUACUGUAUUUCUUCUGUAUAUAUGUGUGUGAAUGUGUGCUUUUUCCUUUUUUUUUUAUCUGUCUACUUAUUUUGGCUAACCCAUUUGAAAGUAAGUCAUAAAAAGCAUUACUCCUAAAAUUUAAUACUCAUCUCCUUAGAAGACCACUUUUCUACAUAAACAUAAUUUCUUCAUGAUACCUGAGGAACCUAAGAAAAAAGUAGCUUGAGACUUUUCUAAAAGAAGAAAAUGAGUGCGGAAUGAGGCCAAAUGGAGUAGUCAGGUAAAACACAUGUUAUUUAAAGACAUGAAUAGAUUGGAAUAGACUUUUAGGCUCUUAUGUCAAAGUUCAAACAUGCUUCAAAUAUUUACAUGAUAAUAUAUAGCAAAAAUCCAUAAUCAAUAAUAGUUACAGAUUAAAAUCUUUAACUUUUAAAAGAAAGAGGUUUUUUGUAGUUUUUACAGAUUUUUACUGUGAUGCCUCAAUUUUGUUCCUAAAACAUUUUCAUUGACUGCUACUCAUCAAGUACUGAGGACAAAAAGAAUAGUUGUUUAAAAAUUUCUGACUUUCAAAUGGGCUUUGGAAAAAGUUCAAUAUGGUAAAAUAUUUUAUUCUUGGAGUCUUUUCUUCAUUUAUAAAGUUUCAAAUAUAAUCUCUGUUUUAGGAAAAGGAGCAAAAGUGACACAAAAUGUACUGCAGCAGUAUUACUGUUUAUGAUAUGAAAUUUUGUAAAAGCAAUGUUGAAAUUUUCCAAAUAGUUGAGGAGACAUUCACAGAAAGACAUACUCAGAAAGAGGAAGACAUGUUUAGAAAGUAGAAAGGCAGCAAAAGAAAAUGAGAUCAGCUUUUAAAAGGUUUCACAUUUUUAGUUGUAAUUUUACAUUAUGUGAAAUUUGUAUUGUGUUUCAGCAUUUUUGAGAAAUGUUUUACAUAUUUACGAACAAAUAUAUAGAAAAAGCAGUGUCCACUUUAGUAAGAUGUGAAGACAUCAUAAAGAAUUUAAAGGUCAACUUAUUCUCUAGAUAUGGUGGUAAAACGUUAUAAGGAUUUGUAAGGGAGAAUUGGAUUAAUUUACAUGUGACAAAUUAUAUGUAAUUAUAUAUAUUUGCACAUAUAUGUAGAUAUGUUUCCAUGUGUGUGUAAUUAUACAUGCAAAUAUAUGUAAUGUAUGGACCCCUGAACUUUAUAUUUUCCUCUUUAGGGAAUUAGAAAGGCAGUGGAGGCCUAUGUCCAUAUAAAUAUACACUUAAGCCUAUUAUAAUUGAGACUACAGAUCAUACUAUAUGAGAGAAUUUAGAUUACCUUCAUGAAAUUAUUUUUUAAAAAUUAUCAAUACUAUAGUGAAGGAUAAAAGACAUGGUCACCAAACAGGAACAAUGGCUUACUUUAGUAUUGUAGAUUUAGUCAUGGACAACAUAUGCCCACAAAAUUCACAUAUUUGGGCUGCUUGUUUUCACAGUGAUAGUUGCAGUGUAUGCAAAUACAGCCUAAGACUGCUGACACACAUCUUCAAAUGCUUUCAAUCAUAGCAUUCUUCCAUUCUAUGUCAUGCAAAUGUGAAUGAAUUUCUGUACUAGUCUUCCCUUAAUAGUGAUUAAGGAAUGCUUUGAAAGCAAAAUAAACUUUUCAAGUUCUUCCUGAAAUGAUUGAGGAGUAUUUUCCAUUUGGUGGGUUUAAUAACACCACUCUUAAAAUCACUGAGAAAAUGAUCAAGAAUGCCUCUGGACUGCAGUUAAUCUCAAAGCAGAUUUGGAACUUUGUGAGUUUGUGGUGUUGGAUGUGGCACUUCGAGUAAGCAAUUGCCAUAAACUCAAGUGGCUGUCAUUUCUUCUGUAGUAUUUGUACACAGUGUAAUAUGAUUUGAUAGCAUUGAUACUGGUGGAAUGGAGAUGUCACUGAUCCCUGCAUAUAAAUCUUGACAUCCUCCAUGUUUUUACAGAAAAACUUAUUUCAAAUCAUCCCCUCUAUUGCAGCAGACUAAAUCUUGAAUUGCUUUUCAUUUAUACCAUUUAAAUCUUGACAGUUUAUCAGAGUACGCAUGUGAGAAUCAGUAAAAGAUGCAGACACUGUUGGUGUAUUUUGUUCUUAUAACCUUGAUCAUUGAUUACUCCGCAUAUUGGAUAUUUUGUAAGCUGCAUGGUGACUAAGAAGGCAUGUGGGGAACUUAAAAAAUAUAUUGCAAGUGCUAUUAGAGUUCAACAAACAUUUAAGGUUAAAUACAACCCACAAUUUUAUUUUGUUCUUAAAAUAGCAGUCUCAAAAGUAUCUGUUGGUUAGUUAACUGACUCCUGCAAAUAAAGUGCUCACUCAAAUGAAUUUAAUUGACUGUUGCCUAAGUGUUAAGCUGUCUUAAAGUACUCAUCACAUAAAAGUGUUUUUAAAUACCCCUGAGUAGGAAGUCUGUUGAAAGCAAAAGAAUGGAAGCUGGUAUAUUCACAAGGGGUGGGUAUCAUUGCAGGAGAUCAGGAUAGGGAGGUGUUUGCCUGGUGACAGCAACAGAGGAGAAGGUUUAAGGAUGAAGUAUGGAGAAUUAAAUGAAAGGGGCAGGCUGGAACCUAGGGUGAAGUGGGAGAGCUUACAAAAGAUUGAACAGAGAUGUGGAAGGAUCUCUAGUGCAGCAGGAUGUCAUGGAAAUUGAGGAAGCAGUUCAGGAAAAGGGAGAGGUGGAAGAAGAGGAUGUCUGAGGAAAAGCCACUGAGGCUUGUGAGUAGGAAGCCUUGAAUUACUGGAAUGUAGGGCUUUAAGGGGGGAAGAAAAUACAUUGAGGUCCGUAAUACUUUGAUAAAACUGAAUUAUACUUACUGACAUGUACACAUGUAUACAGUUGACCCUAGCACAAUAUGGGUGUUAGUGUUACUGAACGGACAGUUCAGUAAAUGAACCGUUUGCUUUCCUGGUGCAGUAAAGCCAAACAUCCACACCAAGGCUUUGCAGUGGGAGAAAGGAGAGUGUUUAUUUGCAGGCAGCCAAGCAAGGAGAAUUGGUCAGCUCACACUUAAGACCUGAUCUCCUCAGUGGCUUAUAAGCAAGAGUUUUUAAAGGUAGUGAUAAGUUUCAGAAAAGCAGAAGUUAAAGGCCAGAUCGUAAGUCAGCACAUGCAGGUUAUACAUUGGUUUGGCCUAAAAAGGUGGGUAUCUUGAAGCAAGAGGAGAGGGAGGUUACAGGUCCCUCUCCUAGAUGGAUUCUGGCUCUCUAAUUUGAGUUUGGUUAAGAAAGUGAAGCUUUGUCUAAAAACUUGGAGUCAGGAGAAAGGACUGUUAAGGUCUGGCCUGUGGGCAUGACUUCCUCUGGGGCCCUCAGGAAGAAAUUUAGAAGCAGGAACUGUGGCCAGGGUUCAGUCCUCAUUUCCCCCUUAUCUGAGGUCUAUAGGCCAGAGGUUCCAUUUGGUAAAGGUCCCUUUUACUGAAAAACAGCUCAGGGAUAUAUAUUAACAUGUUGUCUUUAGUUUCUAGAGGAGCCAGACAUCUUGUGACUCCAACUUCCUUGGAUAUUGUUUUAAGCUAUUACUAUGUUCUUACUUACCAAGUUGCUCAUUUACUUAUCAGGGCUAGCUCAGCGCCUGGAAUUUCCGUUGAAGGAACUCAAGAUUUUUCUUUACUUCUAUGCUUGGGAAGGCCUGGCAGGCCCCUAAGAAGGAUCUCUGCCCCAUCUCAAUAGGUGAGCUUCUCUUACAAGGCCCUGUAUUUAUCAAAGAACCCAGCAACAGCAUUUUCCCUGUUGGUUCAGAAGAUAAAAAAAUAACUUUGCAUUGUGAAGCAAGAGGCAAUCCAUCACCUCAUUACAGAUGGCAGCUGAAUGGAAGUGAUAUUGAUAUGAGUAUGGAACAUCGUUAUAAGUUGAAUGGAGGAAAUCUUGUGGUUAUUAAUCCCAACAGAAAUUGGGAUACAGGAACUUACCAAUGUUUUGCAACAAAUUCACUUGGAACAAUUGUCAGCAGAGAAGCCAAACUUCAGUUUGCCUAUCUUGAAAAUUUUAAAACCAAAAUGAGGAGUACAGUGUCUGUGCGUGAAGGCCAGGGAGUUGUGCUGCUCUGCGGCCCCCCACCACACUCUGGAGAACUGUCAUAUGCUUGGAUCUUCAAUGAAUACCCAUCGUUUGUUGAAGAAGAUAGUCGGAGAUUUGUCUCCCAGGAGACAGGGCACCUCUACAUAUCUAAGGUGGAGCCGUCUGAUGUGGGAAAUUACACAUGUGUGGUGACAAGUAUGGUGACAAAUGCCCGAGUGCUGGGCUCUCCAACUCCUUUGGUGCUACGUUCUGAUGGUGUGAUGGGUGAAUAUGAACCUAAAAUAGAAGUUCAGUUUCCAGAAACUCUUCCAGCAGCUAAAGGUUCGACUGUGAAAUUGGAAUGUUUUGCCCUUGGAAAUCCCAUACCUCAGAUUAAUUGGAGAAGAAGUGAUGGGCUGCCAUUUUCCAGCAAAAUUAAAUUAAGGAAGUUCAGUGGUGUGCUUGAAAUCCCCAACUUCCAACAGGAAGAUGCAGGUUCCUAUGAAUGCAUUGCUGAGAAUUCACGAGGAAAAAAUGUUGCCAGAGGGCGUCUCACUUACUAUGCAAAGCCCCAUUGGGUUCAACUCAUAAAGGAUGUGGAAAUAGCCGUGGAGGACAGUCUUUAUUGGGAAUGCAGGGCAAGCGGCAAGCCCAAGCCUUCCUACCGAUGGCUGAAAAAUGGAGCAGCCCUGGUGCUAGAGGAGAGAACACAGAUAGAAAAUGGUGCCCUUACAAUAUCAAACCUAAGUGUGACUGAUUCUGGCAUGUUCCAAUGCAUAGCAGAAAACAAACAUGGCCUUGUUUAUUCCAGUGCUGAGCUCAAAGUUGUUGCUUCUGCUCCAGAUUUUUCAAAGAAUCCAAUGAAGAAGUUGGUUCAGGUGCAGGUGGGCAGCCUGGUCAGCUUGGAUUGUAAACCCAGAGCCUCCCCAAGGGCACUCUCUUCCUGGAAGAAGGGGGAUGUGAGCGUGCAGGAGCAUGAAAGAAUUUCUUUGUUAAACGAUGGAGGACUCAAAAUAGCCAAUGUGACUAAAGCUGAUGCUGGAACUUACACCUGCAUGGCAGAAAACCAGUUUGGGAAAGCAAAUGGCACAACACAUUUGGUUGUUACGGAACCAACAAGAAUAACUUUGGCACCAUCUAACAUGGAUGUUUCUGUUGGUGAAAGCGUCAUAUUGCCCUGCCAGGUACAACAUGACCCGCUGUUAGACAUCAUCUUUACCUGGUAUUUCAAUGGGGCCCUUGCAGAUUUUAAGAAAGAUGGAUCUCACUUUGAGAAAGUUGGUGGGAGUUCAUCUGGUGAUUUAAUGAUCAGAAACAUUCAGCUGAAACACAGUGGGAAAUAUGUUUGUAUGGUGCAAACGGGGGUGGACAGUGUUUCAUCUGCUGCUGACCUCAUAGUAAGAGGUUCACCUGGACCACCAGAAAAUGUGAAGGUAGAUGAAAUUACAGACACAACAGCCCAACUCUCUUGGAAAGAAGGUAAAGACAACCAUAGCCCAGUUAUAUCCUAUUCUAUCCAGGCUCGGACACCUUUCUCCGUGGGUUGGCAAACCGUCACAACAGUGCCUGAGGUCAUCGAUGGGAAGACGCACACAGCCACUGUAGUUGAGUUAAACCCAUGGGUGGAAUAUGAAUUUCGGGUUGUAGCCAGUAACAAAAUUGGAGGUGGAGAACCAAGUUUACCCUCAGAAAAAGUAAGAACUGAAGAGGCAGUUCCAGAAGUGCCUCCUUCUGAAGUCAAUGGAGGAGGCGGAAGCCGGUCUGAACUUGUGAUAACCUGGGAUCCAGUCCCUGAAGAACUACAGAAUGGUGAAGGUUUUGGGUAUGUUGUUGCUUUCCGCCCUCUUGGGGUUACCACCUGGAUCCAGACAGUGGUGACAUCCCCUGACACCCCAAGAUAUGUCUUUAGGAAUGAAAGCAUCGUGCCAUAUUCACCAUAUGAAGUUAAAGUGGGUGUUUAUAAUAACAAAGGUGAAGGACCAUUUAGCCCAGUGACAACAGUGUUCUCUGCAGAAGAAGAGCCUACAGUGGCCCCAUCUCAAGUCUCUGCAAAUAGCCUAUCUUCCUCAGAAAUUGAGGUUUCAUGGAACACCAUUCCUUGGAAGUUGAGCAAUGGACAUUUACUGGGCUAUGAGGUGCGGUACUGGAAUGGGGGUGGAAAGGAGGAAUCAUCCAGUAAGAUGAAAGUGGCAGGAAAUGAGACAUCAGCCAGACUACGGGGCCUGAAGAGCAACCUGGCCUAUUACACGGCUGUCCGGGCUUACAACAGUGCCGGCGCUGGGCCUUUUAGCGCCACAGUUAAUGUAACCACCAAGAAAACGCCUCCCAGUCAGCCACCAGGAAAUGUUGUUUGGAAUGCCACAGACACUAAAGUGUUACUUAAUUGGGAGCAAGUUAAAGCCAUGGAGAAUGAGUCAGAAGUAACAGGAUAUAAAGUUUUCUAUAGGACUAGCAGUCAAAAUAACGUACAAGUACUGAACACAAAUAAAACUUCAGCUGAACUUGUGCUGCCCAUUAAAGAGGACUACAUUAUUGAAGUCAAGGCCACAACAGAUGGAGGGGAUGGGACCAGUAGUGAACAGAUCAGGAUUCCACGAAUAACCAGUAUGGAUGCAAGAGGAUCCACUUCAGCCAUCUCGAAUGUCCACCCUAUGUCAAGUUAUAUGCCUAUAGUACUGUUCUUAAUUGUAUAUGUCCUGUGGUGAUAUUAACUCCUUUUUAUUAUUUAUUGGAAAGUUAUUUGGUUACCAAAAAAAGUGCUUUCAUGAAAUGCAGUGAUUAUGCAUGUUUUUUUCAACUCUUAUUUUUAACUUUCUACUUCAUUAUAGGUAAAUAUGAAUAUAAUUAAAAAAACAGUAAAUCCUUUUAGGGGAAUCUGAAAUGCCUUAAUAUUAACUUGAUAAACCAAAGGAAUUUACAUAUUACAUACUUCAGACUUUUGAUAUAAAUGUUCUUAAACUAUGAGUUUAAGCACUGCCUAUGGAUAAAGACUCACACACUCUCACAUGUACACACACACGCAUGAGAAUUUCUUUUUACAUUGAAAAACUCUUUCAUUUAAUUCAAAUGCUAUUUUCCCAUUAUAAUAGCAUUAUUUGGAAGACUUAACCAGUAUCAAUUUGAAAUGCUGAUUUAAGUCCCCAAGGAUGAAAAAUACAUUUUAAAAAUUAUUUUGUUGGAGAGGAGUGGCAUGUGAUUCAAAAGAGCAUUGUUGGAAAAUGCUACUGUGGGGCUUAGAAGAAUGAUGUUUGGUUUGGUAUGCUGCUAACUAGUUGUAAGACUUUACAAAUCACUUUGCCAUCUGUACCUCUCAAUUAUUCCUCUAUAAAAUAUGGAGAUAAUAAUACCUAUCUGAUCAGACUUUGCCCCAUGAAUUAGUUUUUAAAAGAUAAAGACUGAAGUAUGAAAGUGCUUUUGUCACCCCAAAUGCAAUUGACCCAUGCAAAAUAUUAGCAUGAAUUUAUUUAAUCACAUAAAAGUCAUGAAGACCAGCCAGAUUUUCAAGCUUCAUUCUGUUUCAUUCAGUUAUAUUCCAAAAUUCAAAUGAUCACAUUUUAUUCUUUCUCAAAAAAAAAAAGUUUUUUUAAAUUAAAAAAGGAAUUGUUUCCUUCACAGCUAUGAAUAAGCUUUCAGGUUUUAUUAAAACCUAGAGGAAAAAAUCAGGAAUGACCUGAAUCUCAACCCAAAUAUUAAACAAAAUCCACAUAAUCCCUCAUUUCAAUUUCCAAUUCCAUUAAGGGACCCUCUCUUUUUGGAUGGCAGAGAUGGUUUUUUAAUGAAAUCCCACCAUCUAUCUGAGUGAGUCUGGCAGGCUUUUUAGUUCCUGAGUUAAAUUUGUAAUAGAACCAAGGCAAUGCUGCUGACUUUGAUAUGUAUGACUCAGUCUUUCAAUAUGUGGUUUUCAAAAAAUUGUUGAAGACGUGACUUCAUAGCAAUAUAUAGAGAAUAAAUUAAAAUCAGCAGAUUGAGUUUUCAACAUUGCAAAAUCAGUUUUUUACCUCUUUCCUACCAAUUUCACAUUUUGCAGAAACUUGUUCACAUUUCCAACAAUAUCAGAAUUAGAAAACAGUUCAGAUAACAAGAAAGAUUAAAAAUUAGGGAAAUUCUGAUAUCACCAUAAAGCACUAUUUUACAUUUAGAGAUUACAUUUAAGAUAAAGUCAUCAUACACAAAAACAAUAAAUAUUUAUAACUUUCUCUAUAAGGUCCGCAUAUACUGUAUAUAUUGAAACAAUCUGAAUGACUAGUAGAUUUCAUAUGACCAUUGUUAUUUCCACUUUCUCCAAUACUUGUAUUUUAUGCUACAUGUAAUGAAGUUGGACCUUUUUAUUAUUUAGUAAUUCCUAUAUGUUCCUAUACUUUUCAUUUUCAAGAUGAUUGCUCUAUUGUUUCAUGUUGUUUCUAGCAAUAUAUCUCCAUGAGAUAUGCACUUUGUUUCAUAUUGAAAAGUAUAAAAUUUAUCUUUCAAUUCCUGUGUGUGUAUCCUAUGGUUAUCUGUAUGUAUUAUUUUCUAUUCUAAUAAAAUUUAUAACAAGCAAA